GCGCGUCCCCGCCCUCGCGUCACGUGACGUGGCCGCGGAACCUGAGCUGCGGGGCCUAAGCCGAGCUAAAUUCGUUGCAGGUGGCCGCGGCGGGUGCAACCACAAAGGCUAAUCCGAAGGAGUCGGGGAGGCUCGUGGAGUCGAUGCUUCCUCUUCCAAGUCAGGUCGGCUCCCGUUACCUUCUCAGCAUUCGCCGUUCCGGUCUUCCUGAGCGCGUGCAUGAGGUCUUUCGCGUGGGGAAGCUCCGGUGACCAUGUAGGGGAGAAGAGUGAGGAAGCUCCUGGUGCUUGGGACGAGGUCAGCGCUGUCGGCGCGCUGCUCCAGCGCCCACCACACCCUGGUGCGGGCCGACGGGCCCUGGGCCCUGGUGGGAGCUCCGGCCUCCGGUCAAGGCCUGGCCGGGAGCGCCACGAAUUCUCGCGUCGUCUCGCGAGAGUCCAAGUUAAAGAACAUGGCGACGUCUAAUCUGUUAAAGAAUAAAGGUUCUCUUCAGUUUGAAGACAAAUGGGAUUUUAUGCGCCCGAUUGUUUUGAAGCUUUUACGCCAGGAAUCUGUUACAAAACAGCAGUGGUUUGAUCUGUUUUCGGAUGUGCAUGCAGUCUGUCUUUGGGAUGAUAAAGGCCCAGCAAAAAUUCAUCAGGCUUUAAAAGAAGAUAUUCUUGAGUUUAUUAAGCAAGCACAGGCACGAGUACUGAGCCAUCAAGAUGAUACGGCUUUGCUAAAAGCAUAUAUUGUUGAAUGGCGAAAGUUCUUUACACAAUGUGAUAUUUUACCAAAACCUUUUUGUCAACUAGAGAUUACUUUAAUGGGUAAACAGGGCAGCAAUAAAAAAUCAAAUGUGGAAGACAGUAUUGUUCGAAAGCUUAUGCUUGAUACAUGGAAUGAGUCAAUCUUUUCAAACAUAAAAAACAGACUCCAAGAUAGUGCAAUGAAGCUGGUACAUGCUGAGAGAUUGGGAGAAGCUUUUGAUUCUCAGCUGGUUAUUGGAGUAAGAGAAUCCUAUGUUAACCUUUGUUCUAAUCCUGAGGAUAAACUUCAAAUUUAUAGGGACAAUUUUGAGAAGGCAUACUUGGAUUCAACAGAGAGAUUUUAUAGAACACAAGCACCCUCGUAUUUACAACAAAAUGGUGUACAGAAUUAUAUGAAAUAUGCAGAUGCUAAAUUAAAAGAAGAAGAAAAACGAGCACUACGUUAUUUAGAAACAAGACGAGAAUGUAACUCCGUUGAAGCACUCAUGGAAUGCUGUGUAAAUGCCCUGGUGACAUCAUUUAAAGAGACUAUCUUAGCUGAGUGCCAAGGCAUGAUCAAGAGAAAUGAAACUGAAAAAUUACAUUUAAUGUUUUCAUUGAUGGACAAAGUUCCUAAUGGUAUAGAGCCAAUGUUGAAAGACUUGGAGGAACAUAUCAUUAGUGCUGGCCUGGCAGAUAUGGUAGCAGCUGCUGAAACUAUUACUACUGACUCUGAGAAAUACGUUGAGCAGUUACUUACACUAUUUAAUAGAUUUAGUAAACUCGUCAAAGAAGCUUUUCAAGAUGAUCCACGAUUUCUUACUGCAAGAGAUAAGGCGUAUAAAGCAGUUGUUAAUGAUGCUACCAUAUUUAAACUUGAAUUACCUUUGAAGCAGAAGGGGGUGGGAUUAAAAACUCAGCCUGAAUCAAAAUGCCCUGAGCUGCUUGCCAAUUACUGUGACAUGUUGCUAAGAAAAACACCAUUAAGCAAAAAACUAACCUCUGAAGAGAUUGAAGCAAAGCUUAAAGAAGUGCUCUUGGUACUUAAGUAUGUACAGAACAAAGAUGUUUUUAUGAGGUAUCAUAAAGCUCAUUUGACACGACGUCUUAUAUUAGACAUCUCUGCCGAUAGUGAAAUUGAAGAAAACAUGGUAGAGUGGCUAAGAGAAGUUGGUAUGCCAGCGGAUUAUGUAAACAAGCUUGCUAGAAUGUUUCAGGACAUAAAAGUAUCUGAAGAUUUGAACCAAGCUUUUAAGGAAAUGCACAAAAAUAAUAAAUUGGCAUUACCAGCUGAUUCAGUUAAUAUAAAAAUUCUGAAUGCUGGCGCCUGGUCAAGAAGUUCUGAGAAAGUCUUUGUCUCACUUCCUACUGAACUGGAGGACUUGAUACCGGAAGUAGAAGAAUUCUACAAAAAAAAUCAUAGUGGUAGAAAAUUACAUUGGCAUCAUCUCAUGUCAAAUGGAAUUAUAACAUUUAAGAAUGAAGUUGGUCAAUAUGAUUUGGAGGUAACCACGUUUCAGCUCGCUGUAUUGUUUGCAUGGAACCAAAGACCCAGAGAGAAAAUCAGCUUUGAAAAUCUUAAGCUUGCAACUGAACUCCCUGAUGCUGAACUUAGGAGGACUUUAUGGUCUUUAGUAGCUUUCCCAAAACUCAAACGGCAAGUUUUGUUGUAUGAACCUCAAGUCAACUCACCCAAAGACUUUACAGAAGGUACCCUCUUCUCAGUGAACCAGGAGUUCAGUUUAAUAAAAAAUGCAAAGGUUCAGAAAAGGGGUAAAAUCAACUUGAUUGGACGUUUGCAGCUCACUACAGAAAGGAUGAGAGAAGAAGAGAAUGAAGGAAUAGUUCAACUACGAAUACUAAGAACCCAGGAAGCUAUCAUACAAAUAAUGAAAAUGAGAAAGAAAAUUAGUAAUGCUCAGCUGCAGACUGAAUUAGUAGAAAUUUUGAAAAACAUGUUCUUGCCACAAAAGAAAAUGAUAAAAGAGCAAAUAGAGUGGCUAAUAGAGCACAAAUACAUCAGAAGAGAUGAAUCUGAUAUCAACACUUUCAUAUAUAUGGCAUAAUUUUGAAUAUCAUGGACAAUAUUUAGAACCCAAAUUUUGGAGUGCUUGGGCAGAAAGUUGUAAAGUUUGUGCUGGAGAAAGGUUUAUUUGGACUUUGAUUACAUAAAUAUUAAAAUCUCUGCCUUACCUUACAAAAACAACUAUAUUUUGCCAAUCACAUUAGUUAGCAUGAUGGCAUUCCCUUCAUGUUGCACACUCUUUGACAGCAUGCUGUUUUGUGGAGAAACUUGCAUUCAUGAAGAGCCCAUUAUCAACUUUUAAAAGUGAAUUUGAUUUGUACCCACCAGGAGAAAUACAGUUGGGAAGGGUGAGGGUGGGGUUCUUGUUGCUUUUUUCUCUUUUUUCCUCUCUUAAAAAAUGUACUUGCACAAGGAAGGAUCUUCAGAUAUUCAUGCACUGAAAAAUGCUGUUAUCUUUUGUUUUUAAAAAAUGCAAUUAAAACUAGAAAUAGCACUCUUGGUUUCUUUUGAUGAAAAGAGUGAGCUGGUCAAUGCAACAUUGGGAAACGGCAGAUGUAGGUGAGAAGUUAAGUAUUUAAUAGUAUCAAAUUGUUCAAACAUUGCUCAGUAUAAUAACUGGAUUUUAAUGGUGACCUAAAAAUGGUAUUAAAUAUUUUCAACUUUCAAAUGUUGGUUUUCUUUAAGCAGGAGACUGCUAUUUUAGUUGUUGUUAAAUGAUGAGGAGUUUUUUUUUUUUUAAAUAUGGCUGGAAAGCUUGUUUUGAAAAAUGAAGCUUAUAUUAAUUGUUGCUUCAAUAGUUUAAAAAAUUUAUGGAGAUAGGUAGGUCAUUAUGAUUGCAGAGCCAAAAUAGCAAAACAAACAUAUUAAGUGUGUUUACUAAACAUAUUGUGUGUUUACUAACACACUUAAUGUUUAUAUACCUAAUAUUUAUUAUGCCAUAUCUGAAUUUAUUAAAAACAACACAGAAAUCUCCUGCUCUGAUAUAGUUAUGUAACUGAUCUCUUAAUCUGUAGCAUAGAAGUAUUUUGGUAUUUUAAGGUCUCAUGAUUAGGGAUUUGUAGCCUCAGGUUUGAAUCAGUCACCUAGGGGUAAGAGAAAAACCACAACAUAAGACCUGAAAAACAGAAGCAAAAUUGUUGCACUCUUAAUACGAGCAGUAAACUUGCCAAAUAUAUGUACAUAUAUAUUUAUAUAUUUUAAAAAUAAACAUUUUUUAAAUCGUCAGAAGGCAACAUUUACCAUGUUCCUUUCAGUCUAUCCAAAGUAGCAACUUAACUAGUUGCUGGCAACUGAAUACCCAGAGUAGUGGAAAUUUUAGGACUUGAGGACGUGAACAACUUGAAAGAGAAAAUUGAUUCCCCUUGAGGAAAGAAUGGCUCAACGUGGAUUUUUAUUCAUUGUGGUGCACGUUUCAAAUUUUCUUGCAAAUUAUUUUAUAUCUUAUUUGAUGUUAAGUAAUAUUUUUAAAGUAUGGUUUUUGAAGAUAGUAGGAAAUGGAGUACAGAAAGGCAUACAGUAUUAUGUUACAGUGGAGUGCUUUCAAGAGCAUUUCGUAGGAUCUGUCCCCAUCCGAAGAGGCUUUGUGAACUGCCUGCUGAAUGGAAGGAAAGCAACUUUAAAACAUUUAGAGUUUUGCUGAGUAUAGCCAAAUGCCUGUUCUGAAACUUAUAGGAAAUUGGAAUUUUGUUUAAAAUUUUACACUUUAAGGUAGCAAAUGUCAAUUAUUAGACCGAGCAUAUUGUGAAGAAUUAAACUAAAAUUAAUACGUACAGUUUUCUCUAAUUAGGUGACUGUUCAUAAUGGGUAUAUUUGGAAUUUAGAAGAAAUAAUUUUGUAGUAAUUGUGGCCCUUAUGUUUAACAGAUAAUUCAGCAUUGGCGUAUUUGCUUGUCCCAAUACAAGAAUGCCAAAGGAGGAAACAGGAAAAAUUGCCGUCCAUUUUAAAAAUUUAGGUUUGUUGUUUUAAACCAUAAUUGUUCUCAGAACUUUUUUGGAACUUCUAAUUUUGGGUCAUUUAAUUUAAGAAUGAGAGUCAUGAUGUUUUGAUUUAUGAAGGUGAAUUUAAUGCAAAAGUGGGUAACACUACAUUCAUAGCAAAGUUUUUUAUUAAAUUUUAUAAAUUUUUAAUAGCCAAUUAUGUCCUAAUUGUAUUUUGGGGAAUGAACAGCAGCAAAUACUGUAAAUGUACAGUUUUCUUUUUUUUUUUUUUUUGGUUAUGUAUACAAAAGUUUUAACUACUUUUUGGUGUUUAUGAAAAUCAUUUAGUUGACAAGGUGCCUAUGCCAUUGUUAAAUUUUCUUUAAGUAAUUUAACAACAGAUUUGCUAAUUUAAAAAAAAAUGAAAAAAAAAAUCUUACCAGCAGUUUGUAAAGGUCUGGAAUCACAGUUGGCAUCCUUUAUUCAGGUCUCUUCUCUCCAGCGUACACUUAAAAUUGGUGCCGAGCAGGGAUAUAACCUGCAGUUAAGUGAAAAGAAAAUCCAGCCUCCCCCUCCAAAAAAAAAAAAAAAAUUUAAUUUUUAAAAAUUAGUGGUAUGGCAAUAAGACACUUCAGAGGCUAUCUUAACCUCUGAAUACCCAUCUUCUAGUUUAAAGACAGAGACAUCCCAUCUGGAAAAUGUUAACUUGUGUUGCCAUCUCGUUGCCGGAGUAAGUAGACAUAAGACAGAGUUUAAGAAGUAAAAAUAUAGAAAAAUUUUGAUGGUCACAAUGAGAUAAAUAUUAGAAUAUUACUAUUCCAAUGAUUAAAUGAGGAUCUUGAAAUAAAUUCUGAAGUCUUCCAAUUUUUACAUUUAUUGGAGGGGUCCCUGAGUUCUGUCAACUUUUUUAUUUAAGUCUCUUGCUCUUAUUUUGUGCAUAAAUGUUAAACCUUCCAAAAAUGAAAUGUUAGCUUUCUUUCUUUUACUUUUUAUUAAAUUUAAUAGAAAAUAUGACCUGAGUAGUUAAAAAGUAUUUUGCAUUAUUUGCAGUAAGAUGUCUCUAGCACUGCUCAAAGGGCAAAUUUUAAAACUUCAGUCUGGGUGAAAGAUUUGCUAGUUUUACAGAAAGAUUUGCUAUCUUAAACUCAAGCUGGUUUUUCUGUUCUCAUGUAAGUGACUGGGAUGCUGUCUUAUGAAUUCUUCCAAGGUCAUGUUUGUGAAAUAAACAUUACAUGAGAGCUUUCCUGUCAUCUACACUAUAUGUUGUCUGGAGUGUUGAACAAAUUUAUUUUAGUUUCUAAGUUGUAAUCUAUCCUCAUAUGGUCUAUACGAUUUUGAAUGUGUGCCACUACAUACUGAGAUGAUAAUGCUGUACAAUUUUAAGUGGUAGCAGUUUCUGUAUGCAGUAGGCUGAAAUAUUUUGAUGAACUGCUUAAUUUUUGGAUUUUAUUUUUUAAGUUGUAUAAUUUAUUUUCUUGCAAAAUAAAAAUGUAAUAUAAAA